GUAGUGUAGUCCUGGCGCCCCGCUGGAGGAGCUCCCCAGCUGGUGGCUGGAGCGACCCCUUGUUCUUUGGUGGCGCUGGUUCAUUCCUGAUGCUGUUAAGGAAUAGGAGGUACUGCCCUGCUGGAGAGGAUUUCCCUUGAUUUUCUUGAACGCUUUUUGUUCUUGUUCUGCCUCCCUGUGGCUCCUGUCUGCCCAGAGAGGACUGCCUGCUGGGGAAAGGGGGUACUCCUGAGCUCCUGACAGCCCAGCUUCAGAUCUACCUUCUGAGAUAUCAUCCUUCUUCAGGGAGAUAAGGAAAAAAAGCCACAGGGUCCCGGAGAGCCAGGGGAAUGCUUCAAAAGUUCUGCUGCCUGAGAGUAACGUCACAGUAAUGGAACGGGAAGAUUCUGGAAUCUGUGUCCCCACCUAGACAACGAUUAUACUGGCAGGAUCUAUCAGGUGUACCUAUUUUGGAACUCUGGAGUCUAGUUGAAGGCCUCCAGUUCCCAGGGGGAAGGAAGCAUGGAGGUGUGUCCUCCAUUUGGAAGUAGUGCUAAGAAAAUUAAAAGAAUAAAACUGGGCAGGGGCAUGAGAAUAGGAUGCAAAGAUGAAUUUUUGGACUGAGUGGCCAAGAAGCUCCAUGGUGAGCACUCACAGUCUAAGGCUGGAAGUUUAAUGAACUGUUUUCUACAUUUCACAGGCACACAUGGCAUUCAGGGAUGUGGCUGUGGAUUUCACCCAGGAUGAGUGGAGGCUGCUGAGCCCUGCUCAAAGGACUCUGUACAGAGAGGUGAUGCUGGAGAACUACAGCAACCUGGUCUCACUGGGAAUUUCAUUUUCUAAACCAGAACUCAUCACCCAGCUGGAGCAAGGGAAAGAGACCUGGAGAGAGGAAAAAAAAUGUUCACCGGCAACCUGUCCAGAUCAUCAAGAAUAUGGAAACAACUGUGACCUACAGAAAGAAGGCAAGCCCAGUGGGAGGAAGAAAUCUAAAAAGCCAAUAGAGAAAUUGAAAUGGAAUUCUAAAAAAAACUAAAAACAGCAGCUCUUACAAUGAUGUUGAGCACAUUAAAAAGAAUGCUGUACAAUCCAAGGAGCAAGUCAUUGUGGUUGCCCAGGAAGCUGUCUUGGAAACCCAAAAUAUAUGUGUAACGGGAGGAAGACUGUUCUAGCAGAUCCAGAGCCAGAGCUCUACCUCGAUCCUUUCUGCCCUCCGGGUUUCUCCAGUCAGAAAUUCCCCAUGCAGCAUGUGCUGUGUAAUCAUCCCCCCUGGAUCUUCACAUGCUUGUGUGCAGAAGGUAACAUCCAGCCUGGGGAUCCGGGCCCAGGGGACCAGGAGAAGCAGCAACAAGCCUCUGAGGGGAGACCCUGGAGUGAUCAAGCAGAAGGUCCUGAGGGAGAAGGUGCCAUGCCUUUGUUUGGAAGAACCAAGAAAAGGACUCUGGGAGCGUUCUCCAGGCCACCCCAGAGGCAGCCAGUCAGCUCUCGGAACGGCCUCAGAGGGGUGGAGUUAGAAGCCAGCCCAGCUCAGUCAGGGAACCCUGAGGAAACAGACAAAUUGUUGAAGAGGAUAGAAGUCUUAGGAUUUGGAACAGUCAACUGUGGAGAGUGUGGACUGAGCUUCAGCAAGAUGACAAACCUGCUCAGUCACCAGCGGAUACACUCAGGGGAGAAGCCCUACGUGUGUGGGGUAUGUGAGAAGGGCUUCAGCCUAAAGAAGAGCCUCGCCAGACACCAGAAGGCACACUCGGGGGAGAAGCCAAUUGUGUGCAGGGAGUGUGGACGAGGCUUUAACCGGAAGUCAACGCUAAUCAUACACGAACGGACACACUCCGGUGAGAAACCUUACAUGUGCAGUGAGUGUGGGCGAGGCUUCAGCCAGAAGUCAAACCUCAUCAUACACCAGAGGACACACUCAGGGGAAAAGCCUUACGUGUGCCGGGAAUGUGGCAAAGGCUUCAGCCAGAAGUCAGCUGUCGUGAGACACCAGAGGACACACUUGGAGGAGAAGACCAUCGUGUGCAGUGACUGUGGCCUGGGCUUCAGCGACAGGUCAAACCUCAUCUCCCACCAGAGGACGCACUCUGGGGAGAAGCCCUACGCCUGCAAGGAGUGUGGGCGAUGCUUCAGGCAGAGGACCACCCUUGUCAACCACCAGAGGACACACUCAAAGGAGAAGCCCUAUGUGUGCGGGGUGUGUGGGCACAGCUUCAGCCAGAAUUCAACCCUCAUCUCUCACAGGCGGACACACACUGGGGAGAAGCCGUAUGUUUGUGGGGUGUGUGGGCGAGGCUUUAGUCUCAAGUCACACCUCAACAGACACCAGAACAUACACUCAGGAGAGAAGCCCAUUGUGUGCAAGGACUGUGGCCGGGGCUUCAGCCAGCAAUCCAACCUCAUCAGACACCAGAGGACGCACUCAGGCGAGAAGCCCAUGGUGUGUGGGGAGUGCGGGCGAGGCUUCAGCCAGAAGUCAAACCUUGUUGCACACCAGAGGACGCACUCAGGGGAGAGGCCGUAUGUGUGCCGAGAGUGCGGGCGAGGCUUUAGCCACCAGGCCGGUCUCAUCAGGCACAAGCGGAAGCACUCGAGGGAGAAGCCCUACAUGUGCAGGCAGUGUGGACUGGGCUUUGGCAAUAAGUCAGCUCUAAUUACACACAAGCGGGCUCACUCGGAAGAGAAGCCUUGUGUGUGCAGAGAGUGUGGCCAAGGCUUUCUCCAAAAGUCACACCUCACCUUACAUCAAAUGACACAUACGGGGGAGAAGCCAUAUGUGUGCAAGACGUGUGGGCGGGGCUUCAGCCUCAAGUCUCACCUCAGCAGACACAGGAAGACCACGUCUGUCCACCACAGACUGCCAGUGCAGCCCGACCCUGAGCCGUGUGCAGGGCAACCUUCGGAUUCCUUAUACUCUCUCUGAAGGCAAAGAUGGGGACAAGGACUAAGAGUCAGAAUGUUGACACUUUGAUGAAAUGGAGUAGAGAAAUGCAUUCUGUAAGUGGUCAAAGGACAUUUGACUGUUUACUUUCUCCACACUAAGUCUUCUCCAUGUUUUGUGGCCUUCGGUUGUAAUAAACUUGGCUUCUUUAUACAUCUGUAA